AGUUCCACUUCCGGCGUAUGAGGCGGUGACAAUGGGAGCAGCGCGGGCGGCGCCGGGAGGCAGCUGACAAGCGUUUGCGGCUUCGCUUCAUGGCCGCUCUCCCGCCCCUCCUGGGAUCUGUGGGGAGCUGGGGAGCCCGCAGCGGCCCGGAGCCGGAGCUGGCGAGCCGAGCGGAGACCUGUGCGCCGCGCCUCUGAGGCGCAGCAUGUGAAGCGGAGACGGCAUCCAGUGGGGGGCGAGCCUCUCAGCCGGCCGGGAUGGCUACCACGGCCGAGCUCUUCGAGGUGGGCCCCGGCGGCUCUACAGGGAGUGGCAGGCCCGGGGUUUGCAGGCAGCUGGGUGGGCGGGCCGAGGAGCGGGCGUUUGCUGGCUGCCCAGGAGGAGCCCUCGGGAGAGAGGAGCCUUUUGUGGCAGAUGAAUAUAUUGAACGUCUUGUAUGGAGAACCCCAGGAGGAGGCUCUAGAGGUGGACCUGAAGCUUUUGAUCCUAAAAGAUUAUUAGAAGAAUUUGUAAAUCAUAUUCAGGAACUCCAGAUAAUGGAUGAAAGGAUUCAGAGGAAAGUAGAGAAACUAGAGCAACAAUGUCAGAAAGAAGCCAAGGAAUUUGCCAAGAAGGUACAAGAGCUGCAGAAAAGCAAUCAGGUUGCCUUCCAACAUUUCCAAGAACUAGAUGAGCACAUUAGCUAUGUAGCAACUAAAGUCUGUCACCUUGGAGACCAGUUAGAGGGGGUAAACACACCCAGACAACGGGCAGUGGAGGCUCAGAAAUUGAUGAAAUACUUUAAUGAGUUUCUAGAUGGAGAAUUGAAAUCUGAUGUUUUUACAAAUUCUGAAAAGAUAAAGGAAGCAGCAGACAUCAUUCAGAAGUUGCACCUAAUUGCCCAAGAGUUACCUUUUGAUAGAUUUUCAGAAGUUAAAUCCAAAAUUGCAAGUAAAUACCAUGAUUUAGAAUGCCAGCUGAUUCAGGAGUUUACCAGUGCUCAAAGAAGAGGUGAAAUCUCCAGAAUGAGAGAAGUAGCAGCAGUUUUACUUCAUUUUAAGGGUUAUUCCCAUUGUGUUGAUGUUUAUAUAAAGCAGUGCCAGGAGGGUGCUUAUUUGAGAAAUGAUAUAUUUGAAGACGCUGGAAUACUCUGUCAAAGAGUGAACAAACAAGUUGGAGAUAUCUUCAGUAAUCCAGAAACAGUCCUGGCUAAACUUAUUCAAAAUGUAUUUGAAAUCAAACUACAGAGUUUUGUGAAAGAGCAGUUAGAAGAAUGUAGGAAGUCCGAUGCAGAGCAAUAUCUCAAAAAUCUCUAUGAUCUGUAUACAAGAACCACCAAUCUUUCCAGCAAGCUGAUGGAGUUUAAUUUAGGUACUGAUAAACAGACUUUCUUGUCUAAGCUUAUCAAAUCCAUUUUCAUUUCCUAUUUGGAGAACUAUAUUGAGGUGGAGACUGGAUAUUUGAAAAGCAGAAGUGCUAUGAUCCUACAGCGCUAUUAUGAUUCGAAAAACCAUCAAAAGAGAUCCAUUGGCACAGGAGGUAUUCAAGAUUUGAAGGAAAGAAUUAGACAGCGUACCAACUUACCACUUGGGCCAAGUAUCGAUACUCAUGGGGAGACUUUUCUAUCCCAAGAAGUGGUGGUUAAUCUUUUACAAGAAACCAAACAAGCCUUUGAAAGAUGUCAUAGGCUCUCUGAUCCUUCUGACUUACCAAGGAAUGCCUUCAGAAUUUUUACCAUUCUUGUGGAAUUUUUAUGUAUUGAGCAUAUUGAUUAUGCUUUGGAAACAGGACUUGCUGGAAUUCCCUCUUCAGAUUCUAGGAAUGCAAAUCUUUAUUUUUUGGACGUUGUGCAACAGGCCAAUACUAUUUUUCAUCUUUUUGACAAACAGUUUAAUGAUCACCUUAUGCCACUAAUAAGCUCUUCUCCUAAGUUAUCUGAAUGCCUUCAGAAGAAAAAAGAAAUAAUUGAACAAAUGGAGAUGAAAUUGGAUACUGGCAUUGAUAGGACAUUAAAUUGUAUGAUUGGACAGAUGAAGCAUAUUUUGGCUGCAGAACAGAAGAAAACAGAUUUUAAGCCAGAAGAUGAAAACAAUGUUUUGAUUCAAUAUACUAAUGCCUGUGUAAAAGUCUGUGCUUACGUAAGAAAACAAGUGGAGAAGAUUAAAAAUUCCAUGGAUGGGAAGAAUGUGGAUACAGUUUUGAUGGAACUUGGAGUACGUUUUCAUCGACUUAUCUAUGAGCAUCUUCAACAAUAUUCCUACAGUUGUAUGGGUGGCAUGUUGGCCAUUUGUGAUGUAGCCGAAUAUAGGAAGUGUGCCAAAGACUUCAAGAUUCCAAUGGUAUUACAUCUUUUUGAUACUCUGCAUGCUCUUUGCAAUCUUCUGGUAGUUGCCCCAGAUAAUUUAAAGCAAGUCUGCUCAGGAGAACAACUUGCUAAUCUGGACAAGAAUAUACUUCACUCCUUCGUACAACUUCGUGCUGAUUAUAGAUCUGCCCGCCUUGCUCGACACUUCAGCUGAGAUUGAAUUUACAAAGGAAUUCAGUGUCAGUUCCUUUACAGAGGAAUGUCUUAUACUUCAGCAGCCCUCGGUUGAUAGAAAGCACAGGAGAUACCUUAUGACACAGCCAACAUUUUGUGAAACAAUGACUGGAACAAAACAGCAGCCAUACUUACCUUUGAGGUUUUAUUUAAAGUUUGGAUACCACUAGCUAUAUUUUGCUUUUUUCCCCUCACAUUGAAUUUUAAUUCCAUUCUUGAAUGUAGAAAUUUCAGAUUCUCUAAAACUACAUGUCACUGUUUUUAUCCUAGAAAAUGUUGCUGUCAGAAGGCAAAGGAAAUGUUACCAGUGUUUUCGGUUCUUGUACUUUUAACAUAUUCCAUUUAGAAAUUUUGCCAUUCUGUUUUCCAUUAAUAAUAGGUGAAAUACAGGAAAACUACAUUUGUUAUUCCUCAGUUUUUAAUGACCUUUUCAGCAUCAAUUGUUAAUCAGAUUAUUUUAGGUUUUCGUAAAUAAUUUUUUUGCCUCUUUCAAAAGGUUAACAAUUAAGCAUACUUUCUGCAGUUGGUUGAUUGGAUUUUUUUCUGAGGUACAGCAUUAAUACUAGUCCAAAAAAUGUCAUAAACUGAACUAAAAUGAUGAACUAUUUUAUGUAGACAUUAGGAGUGGAUCGGAAUACUUCUGCUUUCUGGGUAAAACUUAAAAGUUUACUAUUUCUUAUUUGGUAAAUAGAUUUUAAGCCAAUUCUAGUAAGAAAUUAAUAAAACUACCUUAUUUUGUAUUUCACUUAAGGUGGAGGACCUUAACUAAAGGACCAUAUUUAUUCAUUAUUUUAAUAUUAUAAGGGAAGUAAAAAAAAGUGAGGUAUAGUCUAAAUGGUGCAUAUAGGAAAUACUGACAGUGUUUAGCAACAUGCAGCCCUUUGAGAUUUCUGUCGUAAUGCUAAACUUGAAUAAGAUGGAAUGGCUGAACAUGUGGUUAGUCUUUUAUUUUAAGAAGAAUUGAGAAUUGAUAGAUUUGGAGAUGAGCUUUGCAAAGGCUGUUUGCUUUUCAUGUCUAUAGGUCUGUCAUUGUCCUUUUUCAAAGCAUUUCUGAAGUUAUUCCUACUUGGAUAUAGUUAAUGGAAUUGGCUUAAUUUGAUGACAUAAUAAAUCACUUAUAAAAUUUUAAAUAUCAAGUGAAAAUUUAGAAAGGCCAUUACUAUUCUAUAAACCUUAUAAACUUGCUCUGGGAGAAUGCAUUCUAAAUUAUAUAUAGUGUUUCAGCUCCCAUUGUGGUGUUCAUAGUCUUCUAGGAACAGAUAAACUUAAGUAUUCAAUUCACUCUUGGCAUUUUUUCUUUAAUAUAGGCUUUUUAGCCUAUUUUUGGAAAACUGCUUUUCUUCUGAGAACCUUAUUCUGAAUGUCAUCAACUUUACCAAACCUUCUAAGUCCAGAGCUAACUUAGUACUGUUUAAGUUACUAUUGACUGAAUUUUCUUCAUUUUCUGUUUAGUCCAGUGUUACCAAGGUAAGCUGGGGAAUGAAGUAUACCAACUUCUUUCAGAGCAUUUUAGGACAUUAUGGCAGCUUUAGAAGGCUGUCUUGUUUCUAGCCAAGGGAGAGCCAGCGCAGGUUUUGGAUACUAGAGAAAGUCAUUUGCUUGUACUAUUGCCAUUUUAGAAAGCUCUGAUGUGAAUUCAAAUUUUACCUCUGUUACUUAAAGCCAACAAUUUUAAGGCAGUAGUUUUACUGGCCAUUUAAGCUCUUUGUACAGUGUCAAUUUGUAAAAAAGAAAAAACGAAAAAAAAUCUCAAAUAAAACAUGAGAUAACAUUUUAAGACUUCCAAAUCAGAGAAGUGCUUCAAAUUAUUUUGUUUGGAUUAAUUUUUAAAAUGUAAAGCAUAUACUUGUUGCUUAGUUAUUUUGUUUAUUAUUUUCAUGUUUGAGUUCUGUGCAAUAUUUUCUAUUAUGUCCGUUGAUAGGACAGUGACAAAAUUCGUAAGUGAAUACUUAAUUUAAAAGUGUUAACAUUAAUGCUCAAUAAACAAAUUCCCUGCAGUUGUUUUUUUUAUUUCACUCUUUUUAUAUUUUAGAGCCAUCCAUCCUGAAUUUUAUAAAUGAUUUUUUAUUUAAAAAUUUGAGAUUUUUAAAAUUUUUCACAGCACAGGUCUUCUCAUUUUCUUUUUUAGCAAAAAAUACUUGACUAUAUAAACAAGACUAGAAAUUUAUCCUAAACAGAUGGUCUUUCUCUGAGGGAAAAAAAAAAAUGUGUCAUGUGAGGCAAUAUGCAUUCUUUGUAUUCUGAUUUUUUAAGUGUUUUCAUAUUUAUAGCCAUCACAAAAUUUUGCCCAAAGUGUAUGGCUCAGAAGAGAUGAUCAAUAACUAAAAUGUUUUUCGUUUUGCACAUGGUAAAAUUUUAGGUAGAGAGUGGAGCUUUGUAUAAUUGGUAACUUUAACCAACAUUUACGUAAGUACGGUCUUUGCAGUAUUACACAAUACCGCAUGAGCUAAUAUGCAGUAUUUAGGUAAUGCAUUGAAUGAAGUUGAAAAUAUGCUCUUAACACACUGUGCAUUGUUUUUCUAAAAUUGAGAAAUAUCUGAAAUACAGAAUACGAAUUUAAUAAAGGAAGCCUACCUUAUGUAAAUUAUGAUGUUGAAAAUGACAGUCAACCAGAGUAGAUGAAGUGUCCUUAUGAAGAAUUAUUAAAUAGUAGCUGGAUGGAUCUUUAGAUGGAUGACCACCUGACCAUUCCAGGACAAUUUUUGGUCCCAUUUUGAGGAUUGCCAUAGUUGCAAGUCCUUAGGAUCUUCCUUGUUUUAAAAAACUAUCAAAGUAGGUUAAAUUAAAAUCUAAUUUAAAUUAGGUUAAUUUAUAUUACAUUGUAGAUCAUUCUUUUUUCCCCCCUCUUUCACUUCUAAAUAUUUUGCUUUCUAAAUACUAGCCUUCUGGUUCACAGUGAAAUAAUUUAAUUAUCAAUCAGUAGAUUGAUUCCAAGUGGAGAAUUCACUGCUUCCCUAAAAUGCGUUUUUCUUACCUGUAAUGGUGAAUAUUUACAAGGAUCUGGAUAAAGAGAUUUUGAUUUUUGAAAUGCCACAAAACCCCUUAAAGUGGUCAAGUACCUAAGGUAGUGGCUAAGGCAUGCUUGAACUGUGUUUGAGAGACAGCAGUUCAGUCAGUACAUAAUUUGUUGGUGACUAACAAAGCUCACAUCUGGGAGAUUAACUUUUUUUAACGCAAAAAUAUUCUGCACAUUACCCAUAUAUUGUUGAAUUUUACAUACAAAGCAUUUUGUGCUUUCAUUCAAUUAGUUUAACUAUAUUCAGUUUCUGUAUUAUUUCUCUCUGAUCUAUCCUGUAAUUAUUCUAUACUUUAGAAGAAAAGAUCAGUUCAUAUUGUUAGACUGAAUAAUUCUACAUGAAGUUAAAAGUUAGCAAUUUAAAAAAUUUUGCUGCAUAAUAAAGAUAAUUAUAGUUACAUGUAUUGAUUUAAGUCUCACACACUGUGCUAAUAAGUCCUUUGCACAUAUUAUUGGAUUCUAGAGCAACCCUAGGAUUUGGGUACUAUUAUUUCCAUUUGACAGAUGAAAAACCUAAUGCAUAGAAAGAUAAGUAGACCAGUCAAGGUCUACAGCUAGUAAAAUGCUCAGAUUGAAACCUAAAUCUUUUCUCACUCACUUUUAGGUUCUAUAUGCUAUUCUCCUUACGUAACGUUAAAUAGAUCCUUUAGUUUGAUAGGUUCAUUAGUUUUGCUUAAUCGUUGCUUCCAAUAUGAUUCUUAUUGUAGUAUUUAUAUUACAAAGUUGGCAUACAGGGUCAAUAUCUAAUUUACUGUUGUGUUUUUCUUAAUAUGUUCAAUGUAUGGUCAUACUUUUUAAAUUUGAUUUUUUAAAUAUUAUAAGUGGUCAUGAAAUUUUAAUGUUAAGUUUGUACCUAAUAGAAAUAUGUCUAUCACAAAUCUUUAUUGGUAUUAUUUUAUAUACUUUUCCAGCUUGAUAAUUUUCACAAUAGAAAGAGACCAAAUAUUUUGUACUAUAUUUUGUGACAUAGAAGUAAAUGACAACUCUACCUUGGAAGAUAUGAAGAAAUCAGUGUUUUUAUGUUCAAAAACUAUUUUAAAUGUCAUAGGCUUGCCAAUUGUGUUAACUAUUUAGUACAUUGGUAGUUUUUAAAUGACUAAUGCUGGAGUGAAAAUGUAAGGCAAAAUAUUUAGUAUAUUAACAGUAGAUAGUCAUUUUCAUGUAAUCAGAAUUGCAUGUUAAGGGUUUUAAAAGCUGUCAUAACUCUUACCUUUUAUUUCUACCAGUGAUCAAUCAUUUCUCUUUACAAAUUUAGGGAGGAAACAACUGUUCAAAUGUAUAGGGGACAGAAACCUGACAUUUAGAGAACAGAAAUUUUAAUUGCCAAAUUAAAGCAGCUAGGCUGCCCCUGGGCUUAACAAAAUUCCUAUUUUUGAACUAGACCCGAGGUAUUUUAUCAUUAUUAUUUGAUAGGUACCAUUAACCUUUGUUUUGUGAUUAUCGACUUUUGGGGGGAAAGAUGAGUAAUUAAACACACUCGCCCAUUUUCUAAGUGGUUUAGAAGGUUGCAGUCUGCCUCACCAUACAAAGCCAGUUUAAAUAGGAAUAUAUCACAUCAUACUUCACAUAGCAGUCAACCUCAGAGGAAAGUCAUUUAUUCAGAAGGCAUAGAUUUUGCUAGACAGCAGUGAUGCAUUACAAAUAUAUAAUUAUUUGCACUAAUAUUUGAGCAGGUGGAAUGGAUUAGAACAUGGUCAACAUCAUGCUGCUGAUAACAUGUAUUUUUCUAUAUUAAUAUGUACUGUGCAACAUGUAUUAAAAUUGUCAAUAAUUCAUUUUAGCCAAGAUACUAAUAUUUAUAUUACUGUGUUUAAGAGACAGUAUCCAACUGAGCCACUUUUAAUUUAAAAGUCUGAAACUGGAAUUAAGUUUACUUUCAAAAAUCACUUAAAUUACUUUAUAAUCAGUGAAAGGUCAGUAAAAUGUAGAAUUAUAAGUGCCUAGUGACUUAAUAGGAGGAAAUAUGGAGGGUUAAGGAAGGAAGUAGGAACCUGGAAUAAGAAAGCUAAGUUUCAUUUAUAGUUCCAAUGAGUGACUUUCUUUGUUUUCACCACUGGGAAUCUUAAAUGAAGAAAGUGUCGUAUCCCUUCCAGUUAUCUUUAUGUUAAUAAACUAAGUGAAGUUUGGAUAGAACUAACAAAGGAAUUAGUCUCCAUUGGUGGACUUCCAGAGUUUUGAGAUUAAACUUUGAGAGGUGAGAAGCCUUCCUGAUGCCCCUGUAAUCUUAAAUUGGCAGGUGCCUCUAAGUGAGGCCAUCCCUCUUUGCCUGCCUAUCAUUUUAAUCUUUAUACUGUAACUGGUUCCUUUCAACUCUGGCCUUUUAUUGUAGCACUUUUAUCAAGUCUGCAGCUUCCCAGCUACUUGGGAGGCUGAGGUGGGAAGAACACUUGAAGCUAGGAGUUCAAGACCACUCUGGGCAACAUAGUGAGUCCCUGUUUUUAGAAAAAUAAAUAACCUUUAGGUUUUUGCUAUAGAAAAUAUCCAAAUAGAGUCUGGACAAUGCUGGAUGUAAAGAAAACUGUGAAGCUACCUCUAAGCAUAUUGUUUGUGAAUACUGUGUACCAUUUAGAGGAUAACAUGGGGGAUUCACAUGAAGUUAUGUGAAAAUAUUUUAUAAGGAAUAAUACCUAAGUGCCUCUCUUAAGUUCUCCAGUAGAAUGUAUUUUCAAUUUUUGCCACAAGGGGGAGAAGUUAUUUUUAUAGUAAUAUGUACAUUUUUUUAUUUUAAAAAUAGAAUUCACACAACUUUACAGCAUCUAUGAACAUUUUGCUAUCCCAAUUAUGUGUGUGUGUGCAUGUGUGUAAACAAGAUUCUGAAAGUCUUGCAUGAGAAAAAUUUCAAAGGAAAUUAAUAACAAAACCAAAACAGUUUUGAAGAACAUGUGCACAGUGGACACAGGAAUUGAACAAAGUUUACCAUGAUUAACAUUAUGUUUUCUUAGUUAUAUAUCACAUUGAAUUCCUUUAUCAACUCUAAUAAGAAUCUACUGAUUAGUGUUCUACAUUCUGCUUUUUAAAGAAAAAUUUUUGAAACAAUCAGACUUAACAGAAGGGUUGUAAAUACUGUACAAAUAAAAUUUUUCCCUUUUGAGAAUAAGUCGCUGUCAUGAUGCUGCACCACCCUCCAAUACUUUUGUAUUUCCAAGAAGAAAGAAUGCUUCAGUAUAACUACAAUACAUGAAAAUUGGGAAGUUAACAUUGACAUAUUACUACUAUCUAAUCCUCAGACACCAAUCAUUUUACUAGCUGUCCUAAUUCCUUUUAAGGAUCUCAGUUCAAAAUCAUGUAUUGCUUUAGGUUGUAGUGGCUCUAGUCUCAUUCAUUCUGACACAGUUCCACAGUCUUUCCUUGACUUUUUUGACUCUGGACAUUUUUAUAGAUUAUAGGGUAGUUACUUUGUAAAACACCCCUACAUUUGGAUUUCUGUUUCCACGUAAUUAGAUUCUGUUUGUGCUUUUUGGCAGACAUACCACGGAUGCAACUCUGUGUUAUUGUUGCAUCCUAUCACAUAGUACACAAUUUCAAUUUGCCCCAUUUCUGAUGAUGUUCAUUUUUAUCACUUUCUUAAGGUACUAUUUACCAGGCUUCUCCACUUUAAAACUAUUACUUUUCCCUUUGUAAAUAUUUUGGAGGUAGAUAUAUAUUAAUAGAUACAGACAUAUAUAGGUCCCCCUUAUUUAUUUAUUUGCAGACAGAGUCUCGCUCUGUUGCCCAAGCUGGAGUGCGGUGGCGUGAUCUCAGCUCACUGCAACCUCUACCUCCUGGGUUCAAGCGAUUCUCCCACCUCAGCCUCCCAAGUAGCUAGGACUACAGGCACAUGCCACCAUGCCUGGCCAAUUUUUCUAUUUGUAGUAGAAAUGGGGUUUUGCCGUGUUGGUCAGGCUGGUGUCAAACUCCUAGCCUUAAGUGAUCUGCCCACCUCAACCUCCCAAAGUCCUGGGAUUACAGGUGUGAGCCACCUUAACCAGCCAUCCUUUAUAUAUAUAUAUAUAUAUAUAUAUAUAAUAUUAAUAUAUAUAAAAAUAUAUGUAUAUGUGUGGUGUGUGUGUAUAUAUAUACAUAUGUGUGUGUAUAUACACGUGUGUUUAUACACGUGUGUGUACAUAUACACGCGUGUGUAUAUAUACACACGUGUGUGUGUGUAUAUAUAUAUACUAAUCAGAAUUCUCUUGAUAUCACUAUGUAUUCAUAGUUUUCUGUUCAACUAAUUAUAAUCUGUCAUUUUACCAAAUCUCAAAUUAUCCCAAAUUUGGUCAGAAGUAGCCUCUUCAGGUUGUCUCCUGUGUCGUUUUGGCAUGUUCCCAUCAUUUUUACAGCAAUUUAUUCUGGGCACAACAGGAUUUUCCAAGGUCAUCUUGUACUUGCCUUGCCCCAGCUCUGGAAUCAGCCAUUCCUCCACCUUUUAGUGAAAUUGGCAGUUAGAAAUCAAGAUUUGUGCAUGAGAUGUGCUUAUUAUUAUUGAGAUGUCUCACCCUACUCUUUCUCAAUAGAUAAUGCUAGGGGGCUUUAUGUGUGCAUACACACACACACACUCACGCAUAUUUUAAAUAUACACCCACACCCAUGCGCCCCUCUGCAACAUCUUCCUCACCUCACUUGAGCUUCCAUACUCCAUACUGGGCUUCCCCUCUCUCUGGAGGAGACCAUCCUCAUCUCACAUAGCUCUUGAAGUUUUGGCUUUAGGACCAAAUUGAGGGAAUAAGAAUGGUCAUUGCAGAAAUCCUGUAAAAAUUUUAAAAUAUUAAAUUUAAAAAUUACAAUUUUAUCACGCAGAAACAACUAUAUUUUUGGUGGAAGUUUUUUUUUUUUUUUUUUAAUGUAGUGAGCAAAUUAGUAAAGCUGAAUUGAGGAGGGGGUAAAGUGUUAUGCCCAAGACACAGAACUUACAUUUUGAAAGAAUUAAAUUUGAAAUGCAUACCGUAUGUUUUUCUAUUAUACAAUCUCCUUGCUACUGUAAUUGCUAUUUAAUAAGAGUGCAUCAGAGAAACUGUAUGAAUGGAAACCUGACCAUUAAGCACUGAAUACCAAUAGGAUAUUUUUACUAAUAAAGUUCAAAGGAAAAAUGA